AUGACCCACUGCUGUUCCCCUUGCUGUCAGCCUACAUGCUGCAGGACCACCUGCUGCAGGACAACCUGCUGGAAGCCCACCACUGUGACCACCUGCAGCAGCACACCCUGUUGCCAGCCCUCCUGCUGUGUGCCCAGCUGCUGCCAGCCUUGCUGCCACCCAACUUGCUGUCAAAACACCUGCUGCAGGACCACCUGCUGCCAGCCCACUUGUGUGGCCAGCUGCUGCCAGCCUUCCUGCUGCAGCACACCCUGCUGCCAGCCCACCUGCUGUGGGUCCAGCUGCUGUGGCCAAACCAGCUGUGGGUCCAGCUGCUGUCAGCCUAUUUGUGGGUCCAGUUGCUGUCAGCCUUGCUGUCACCCGACUUGCUAUCAAACUAUCUGCUUCAGGACCACCUGCUGCCAGCCUACCUGCUGCCAGCCCACCUGCUGCAGGAACACCUCUUGCCAGCCCACCUGCUGUGGGUCCAGCUGCUGCCAGCCUUGCUGCCACCCAACAUGCUGUCAAACCAUUUGUAGAUCCACCUGCUGCCAACCAUCCUGUGUGACCAGAUGCUGCAGCACACCCUGUUGCCAGCCAACCUGUGGUGGGUCCAGCUGCUGUAGCCAAACCUGCAAUGAGUCCAGCUAUUGUCUGCCUUGCUGCCGUCCCACCUGCUGCCAGACCACCUGCUACAGGACCACCUGUUGCCGCCCCAGCUGUUGCUGCAGUCCUUGCUGUGUCUCCAGCUGCUGCCAGCCUUCCUGCUGCUAA